GACAGACGCAAGAUGGCGGACAGUGCGGAACUAAAGGUAAAGCGCAGCUCGAAUUCACUUCUAAUAUUCGGCCGCGGAGACGGCGCCGCUGCUGCCAGGGGGGAUGGGUCCGACCCUGGGGGGCCUCUCGGGCCUGACUCCACCCGGGCCUGGAGUUGUAGGGAGAGAGGCGCGCCCGGUCUCAGCAGAGGGGGCCCGCCUGCGGCGGGCCGCGGGCCCCGGGUGCCUCGGGGGCGCUGACGGGUCGUCCCCGGCGUGUUAUUGUUGUGGGCGCCUCUGGCGGGGGUGGCGGGGGAAGAGAUAGGGAGUCCGGAGGUAGGGGCUGCAGCUGUCUCAUGGGCUCGGCUUUUUCACCUUCCAGUUAGCCUCCCUGCCCCCCAUGGGGAGCUGGGGCUGGGGGCAGGGUGCUCUCGUAGGGGGGAUUGGGAAAGCUCCCCGUGGCCGCUUCCUCUUCCUCCUUUGCAGUCCCGGGCUCCUGUCAGGCGCUCUUCUCAGACCCCCGGGAACUUGGCUUCGGCCGCCCCGCCCCUCCGUGGAUCCCAGUAGCCCCCGCCCCGGACUCGGCUUUCCCCGGCUGCUCGCUUGUCAGGAAGCGCCUGGGGUGCCCCGCUUGUGGGAAGCGCGAUCCCGGGGCGAUAGGGUGGGGAUCUGGGGGAGAAGCUCUGGUAAAGUUUAGCGAGCCCCGGGCCGGCGUUGGGGUUCGGCUGAGAGGUAGUGAGCGGGACGUUACUCUUUCUCUCUGAUUCCGGGCAGCCGAGGGGAGAAACCCCCUCGAAGAGUGUGUCUUUGGAAGCAGUGUUGGGAGGGGGGGAUGCAGCUACCUCUCUCCCUUCUUUUGCCUUAGCUGGUGUGGAGGGUGAGAGGAGCCUUUGGGGGUCUCUGCACACACCAUGAUGGCGAUGCUGUAGCUGAUGGAGGUGAAUGGUUCGUGUUUAUAUCCCCCCAUUGCCUUUUGUUUGUAGGGACAUCUUGCUGGCCAUGUUGAUUUGAACGAAAUUCUCCCCUCAUGCUACUCCAACCCCCGAUAAAUAGAACGUUCCUCUUAACAGUACCAAUUACUCACGCCUCACGAAAUUAGAUGAAAGGGUGCCCCCUUUUCCCCGCUUUUCUCCCACCCCAAUCUUUACCUGAUGAUGGCUUCUUUACCGUAGCAGAUAUACCACUACACAAGCAGUUGGGGGAGGGGGUGGUGGAACCCUUAUGACUGGAUUGUGACAAAUGGGGCUCCGCUUGAAUAAUUUUGGUUUAGUAGCAGGCAGUUCUUAACUAACGCGUAUUAUUUCGAGGCUCUGAACGCGAUCUUCUCUGUGGCUUCCUGUGUGUGUGAACCCAGCAGCUGGUUAUGUCUCGACCCAGAGAACUGACAUCUCUGUCAGAGAGGAGAUGGGGAUAUACAAUUGUAAAUCUUUGGGGAGAGUCUUCUUUUUAUAAUAAAUAAAAAUUAUUUAAUUUUUUCCCCGUUAUAAUGAAACGACAACUUCUAGAACAACCAAAUGCCAGAUUUGAUUCUGUAGAGUUUUUCCUGUGGAAUAUCCUCACCGAAAGAGCUUUUCUCCUAAUAACUUCACAAUGUUUACACUCCAAGAUUCGUAUGUUAAGCAAAUGGUUAUGAGCCUUAGAGUUUCUGAACUCCAAGUACUGUUGGGCUACGCCGGGAGAAACAAGCACGGACGCAAACACGAACUUCUCACAAAAGCCCUGCAUUUGCUAAAGGCUGGCUGUAGUCCUGCUGUGCAAAUGAAAAUUAAGGAACUCUAUAGGCGGCGGUUCCCACAGAAAAUCAUGACGCCUGCAGACUUGUCCAUCCCCAACGUACAUUCAAGUCCUAUGCCAGCAACUUUGUCUCCAUCUACCAUUCCACAACUCACUUACGAUGGUCACCCUGCAUCAUCGCCAUUACUCCCUGUUUCUCUUCUGGGACCUAAACAUGAACUGGAACUCCCACAUCUUACAUCAGCUCUUCACCCAGUCCAUCCGGAUAUAAAACUUCAAAAAUUACCAUUUUAUGAUUUACUGGAUGAACUGAUAAAACCCACCAGUCUAGCAUCAGACAACAGUCAGCGCUUUCGAGAAACCUGUUUUGCAUUUGCCUUGACACCACAACAAGUGCAGCAAAUCAGUAGUUCCAUGGAUAUUUCUGGGACCAAAUGUGACUUCACAGUACAGGUCCAGUUAAGGUUUUGUUUAUCAGAAACCAGUUGUCCACAAGAAGAUCACUUCCCACCCAAUCUUUGUGUGAAAGUGAAUACAAAACCUUGCAGCCUUCCAGGUUACCUUCCACCUACAAAAAAUGGCGUGGAACCAAAGCGACCCAGCCGACCAAUUAAUAUCACCUCACUUGUCCGACUGUCCACAACAGUACCAAACACGAUUGUUGUUUCUUGGACUGCAGAAAUUGGAAGAAACUAUUCCAUGGCAGUAUAUCUUGUAAAACAGUUGUCCUCAACAGUUCUUCUUCAGAGGUUACGAGCAAAGGGAAUAAGGAAUCCGGAUCAUUCUAGAGCUUUAAUUAAAGAGAAGUUGACUGCGGAUCCAGACAGUGAAAUAGCUACAACCAGCCUAAGGGUUUCUCUACUAUGUCCACUUGGUAAAAUGCGGCUGACAAUUCCGUGUCGGGCCCUUACAUGUUCUCAUCUACAAUGUUUUGACGCAACUCUUUACAUUCAGAUGAAUGAGAAAAAACCAACCUGGGUUUGUCCUGUCUGUGAUAAGAAGGCUCCAUAUGAACACCUUAUUAUUGAUGGCUUGUUUAUGGAAAUCCUAAAGUACUGUACAGACUGUGAUGAAAUACAAUUUAAGGAGGAUGGCACUUGGGCACCGAUGAGAUCAAAAAAGGAAGUACAGGAAGUUUCUGCCUCUUACAAUGGAGUCGAUGGAUGCUUGAGCUCCACAUUGGAGCAUCAGGUAGCGUCUCACCACCAGUCCUCAAAUAAAAACAAGAAAGUAGAAGUGAUUGACCUAACCAUAGACAGUUCAUCUGAUGAAGAGGAAGAAGAGCCAUCUGCCAAGAGGACCUGUCCUUCCCUAUCUCCCACAUCACCACUAAAUAAUAAAGGCAUUUUAAGUCUUCCACAUCAAGCAUCUCCAGUAUCCCGCACCCCAAGCCUUCCUGCUGUAGACACAAGCUACAUUAAUACCUCCCUCAUCCAAGACUAUAGGCAUCCUUUCCACAUGACACCCAUGCCUUACGACUUACAAGGAUUAGAUUUCUUUCCUUUCUUAUCAGGAGACAAUCAGCAUUACAACACCUCCUUGCUUGCCGCUGCAGCAGCAGCAGUUUCAGAUGAUCAAGACCUCCUACACUCGUCUCGGUUUUUCCCGUAUACCUCCUCACAGAUGUUUCUUGAUCAGUUAAGUGCAGGAGGCAGUACUUCUCUGCCAACCACCAAUGGAAGCAGUAGUGGCAGUAACAGCAGCCUGGUUUCUUCCAACAGCCUAAGGGAAAGCCAUAGCCACACCGUCACAAACAGGAGCAGCACGGACACGGCAUCCAUCUUUGGCAUCAUACCAGACAUUAUUUCAUUGGACUGAUUCCCAGGCCCUGCUGCUCCCAUCCCCACCCCAGAUCGAAUGAACUUGGCAGAAAGAAGAGAACUUUGUGCUCUGUUUUACCUUACUCUGUUUAGAAAAGUAUACAAGCGUGUUUUUUUUCCUUUUUUUAGGGAAAAAAUUAAAAGAAAUGUACAGAGAACAAAACUAUAUUUUCAGUUUUACUUUUGUAUAUAAAUCUAAGACUGCCUGUGUGAUAAAACACUUGUUUAAAAAAAAAAAGGAAAGAAAAGAAAAAAGAAAAACAAGCACCCACAAACCACCUUCAGUUCAUUUUUUUCUGGAUUCUGAAGAUUUUUCAUUAUUUGUCCUAUGGUUUUGGUUUUAUUUGACUUCGAUGGCAUUAUUUUAUUUGCAAUAACAGAAAAGGAAUUGCAUGUAUGAAGUUUUCAAUCGUGGGCUUUUCUUUGUUGUGGGGAGGGGGUCGGGGGAUAGUUUGAUUUCCAUUUUCUGAAAACGACAGACUUGGAUUCUGUUUGUGUGUGCAUAUUUUAUCCAGCCUUAAGUUAUAAAGCUCAUCUGUCCCGCUGCAUUCCCUGUGUAUUUUCAGGACAUGGCUCGUGGGUGUGUGUGUUCAUUGUGUGCGUCUGUAUGUAUUUUUCUGUCAUCACUGUUCCCUCUCCUCCCGAGUGUGCAUUCAGUUAAUAUAAUCAGUUGCUUGCUUCUUUCAAAGUGCUUUGAAGGUCUUGAACUCACGUGUGAGCAUCUUUAUCAACUAUCCCAAUUGCAUGUUCUCCAUCACAUAUUCUCUUAUUUGCUCUGUACCCCCUGAGAAUAUGUUUUAGAGAUAUUGGAAUAAAGCUGUCUGGGUAAGGAGUAGGCUUAGCCGACCUAUGAAUAAUACACUUUAGUCUAGUUCUUUAUUCUAAAUCUGGAUUGCCAGUAUUGUGUAUUUAAACCAAGUCUGUGAAUACCUGCUUUUUUUGGCCACAGAGUAACAAGUUUUCAUGUAAGAUCUUCAUACCAAAGUAGGAAGUAAAAAUAGCUUAGAAAGCUCUGUCAGGUGUUUUGUGCAGCUGACAGAGGUAAUGUUACAUCACCUAAAAAAGAAAGAUACACGGUCAGUUAUCCUAAAAAUAAAUUGUUUGGAAAGUACAAUGCACCACAUUUUUGUAGAAGUCUACUAUUUGAUAAACAGUUGAAAUUCAAGAUGUGUUUGACCCUUAGUCAUUUUUACUCUUUGGUUCUGAGUAUACCUAUUUUCUUAGCGUAUCUGCCUUGUUUAUCUUUUUCUUCACCUUUUAACAAGUAUGACAUAGGAAAGUCAUUUUUUUUUAGAAUUCAUGGAUCAGUCUGAUCUACUCUUAUUCAUAAUGGAACAUGUAAAUAUACUGAAAACUGUUUUUCAGGAGAGAAAUAUGAGUUGGAGGGAAGGAAAAGUGGUUCUACUAAUGUUCCAAAAUCCUCAUCAGAGAAGGUAUGAUGUUCUCAGGUGUGGAAAAUAUUUUUUAGUUGAUUGAGAAUGCAGGUUUAACAGAAGAGAUAAGGGGCAUAAUGACUGCUGGUUUUCCAGACUGGAUUUUCCUACCGCAACUAUUAAUGUUCUCAGAGUUGAUGAGGACCACCUUUGUGUAUACACUUGUAGUUUUAAACCUUGCAUUGGUAACAAAAUGAUCAACUUUAAUCCAGGUAGAAUUCAAGAUGGCUGUACUUCAGUUGUAUGAUAAAAUUAAUGGUUCUCAUGACUUGUGUGGCAUCUAAAAAUAAUGUUUUUAUAGCAUCUCUCUGCCACUAAAUUGUUGACUUGAAUUUUGGGAAAAAAAAAAGUUGGUGUUGAUAUGUAUAUGUGUGUGUGUAUAUAUGUAUUUAUAAACAAGUGUGUUUGAGUAACAAGUGAGUUUCAUAGUCUUCCCCUACGCAUGUGUAUUCCACACACAAAUGGCUGAGUUAUAGUCAUAAAACAAUUUGCAAUAAAAAAAAAACCAAAACAGAUUGUCAGUUAACCAGGAAACAGUUAAUGUUUUUUAAUGAAUCUGGCAUUAUAGUGAGCAAAUGUCGUAUUAAUUUAGGCUAAUUUCUAAUACUACCAUAAUUUGUGUCUAAAUUUCUGUUGGGGUAGAAAUUACUAAAAUUGUGGGGAGUUUUUUCUGAUUUUUACAUUGCUUUAGGAAACAUUUUUACUAAUUCAGCUGUCUUAGGUAAAAUGAAUAGUUUUCUUCCUGUUUUUUUAUGUGUCAUUGUUAGUGGUCUCAGAAUUCUGAUCAGUAACUUUGUGUAUGAUGCUGAAUUACAAACCGUUUGAAUGAUCCAGUUGAAAACGUAUCCCUCUACUUUCUUCAGUUGUAGAAAAGGUUAAUUUCCCUCAGUGUCCCACAUUAUACCAACCUAAGAGAAGAACAGGUAAUAGGGAGAAAUAAACAUACGGUGGUUUCAGUGGUUUUGGUCAUGUGUCCACAGGAGAAACUAACCAUUCAGUUGUCUUAAUUUUAGUUCGUUCUACCCUGUGAGGAGUUUGUUUCCAUCAGUUGUUGACUUUCCAAAAUGUUGCAUUAAGUAAUAGUUGUCACUCUGUUGGUCUCAUGGUCAAUAUCAAUCAGACUUUCAUGAUCUCUACUAAUUAUUAGUAGAGUCCUGUACUAUGUCUGUAACUACUAAGUUUAAAGAAAAGCACAUAGUCACUUCAUCUCUUUUUUUCUUAGCCUACGCUCACUCCCCAACCCAUCCCAACAUUGACAUGCUAUCUGUGGACAAAUAGCAGUUCUCAGAAUCUAGUCAAGUUGCCAUCAUCCCCCUUGCCUUGGCCGUUCAUAGUAGGUAUGCAUAUGUUUGUUUCUGUACAGUACUGUGUGUGUGUGUGUGUAUAUAUAUAUACAUCUGUAUGCACACAUCUUUGAUAAAAUAGCUAUUUGACUAGCAGGGUUAAAGUGGCUUUUAAUUACUUCGUGAGUGUUAUUGGAUACAUCUUAAAAAAAAAAAAUCUGAACCAGAACCAUGCCAUACUUGGUUGACUAUUUUGAGCAUUAAAAUUGCUUUACUAAUUAUUUAGACAUGAUCACAAUUCUGUAUCUUUACUGAGGAAAGAUUCACGUAAGCUCUGAAAAAUCGGAUUCUUUGGCAGAUUUUCCUUUGAGUCAAGUGUCUGAAAUGGAGUGAAAAUAUAUCCUAACUAAAUUAAUGUGGAAAGAGCAUUUUUUUAGACAAUUUCAAUUUUAAACACAUAAAACUUUCAAGAUCUUCAGGACUUUUUAAAGCACAUUUGAAAUUAUUUUAGUAAGAAUUUUGUUUUAUCAAUAGAUGUUGAAUUCUGUUUUUUAAUUAAAUACAAAGCUUAGAUUUCAGAAAGAGAGGGAAAAUAGCUGGUGGUCCCAGAGUGUGCUGCUGUUAAUUGUUUAACAAAGGGGAAAAUGUACAUAAACAGAUAAAGUUACCAUAAAUUCCAUGAACUUAAAUCUGUGAUUCAUUGCCUUAAAACUUUCUCUCUUAGAAUUUCCAUACCGCAUGCCAAACCAGUAAAAUGGCUUUUAAAAAUGUAUAGUAGACAAUGUCAGUUUGUAUAAAAGUACCAAGUGAAAAUAUUUAUUACAUGCAUUGGAAAAAAAUUGUUUACCUAUUGAAUGUUACCUGUUUAUGUAGAGCUCUUUAGAUGUAAUAAAAGAAAAGCCUUCAGUUAAUUUGUCUUCUGUAAAAUAACACUGCUGGAUGUUCAAGGGGACAAUCCCUAUGAGACAAGUGAUAAUGGUUUGUGCUUCCAAAGCACCUUUCAUCCAGAGAUUUCAAAGCAUGACAAGUAACUAACUAAUUUUCUUGCAGCAUGCUUUGAGGUAAGUAAUGAAUAUAGCCAUCAUUUCCCUUUCUUGUUGAAAUAUGGCUAACUCUUUAAUAAAUCACAGCAUCUGUUUAGUAUCUGCAGUUUGAAUGCUAAGAGCACCGUGGCCUUCUUGUAAACAACACUAGGUGCUAGAGAAACCAGCUGGAAUUUCAGGAAUGAGCUUGAAACCAGGACCAGGAGUAAGGUAACAGCCCUUCCUCGGGUAGAGGUUUGAAUCAAACACUUAAUAGGAUCUUAGACUCUGGACCACUGAAUCCCUUAAUGAGCAGGGAGUCCGUGAAGAGGAGCCCCAGGUUCUAAUGACCAUUCCACACCAACUGUGUGUUUUUGGCAAGUUAUAUUUCAGAUUCCUGUUAGGCAAAUGAGAUUCAUAAAACUUGCUUUAAAACCAUACUGGGACUAUUCAGUGAUAAAUAUAGACAUAGAAAAGCUUUGACGGAAAGUACCCUCAUUUAUUAUAUCCAGAACUUGCUCUUCCUGUGCCAUCUAAAUCAUUGGUAUCUAUCUCCCAUCUAAUCUUUGGUAUUCCAGGUUGGCUGUGCAGGAUUUACUUCCUAAUGUCCAUGACUGGAGCUCAAAAGAACUGUGGGCCUAGGACCUUUGAGCUUUGCCUGAAAGUGACAGCAGUUCUCUCGGCGGGGCCAGCAUCUAACCGGCCCUCUGGUGGAUUUACCAUGAAGGUAAUGAAGUUUAAGCACCAGGACCCUUCACUUGUUCUGGUCCUAGGAGCAGCCCCAGAAAUUCUGCAUUUCUGUUUUUGUAUUCUUAAGGCAGCCAAAUCUCGUAAACCUCAGACCCCACAAAACAUCUGCUCCUACACUGUGUGGACCUGGGCUUCCCAGCCAGAUGGUCACAACUUCACCUAGUUGGCAUUUGGGCCAUUUAUUUACCCUCACCCCACAAAACUCUUUGGCUCCUAGGAAUUCCUCCUCUCCUUGCAGUUAUGCUUGGGGAAAUGAGAGUCUCCUUCCUCAGGGCCUUGUUUGGGUCUGAAGCCACACAGCAUCGUUGAGACAGUUGCACUAACACUACAACUCUUGUUCCCUGCAGUUUUCCCUGUGCCCGGUGCCUAGUGAAAGAUUUGUGUCUUGUACAUCCUCCCAAAAGACACAUCCCAUUUGAUUUGGUUUUCUUCUACUUUAGCCACUGUGGUACUACUAGACAAAGCCACAGCCCAGAGAACCCACUUUUGAUACAUACAUGGAUGCAAAUCUUUGUACUUGAAGCCCUGCACCCCUACCUGUGUUGGUGUGGUACUCCAGCCCUUUUAGGACUGUGCUGGCACUACGAAUGAUCCAGAUUUGACAAGUGUAUGGCACCUCUGAAUCUCUGGCAGCACCAACCUGGCACCUUCUAGCUGUGUAACUCACUCAAAGCCACUCCAGCUGGAUGGACUCCCAGAAAGCCUAGUGCUCCUACUACUGUUUUCCAGGGCUGUUGUACCCUGGCCAUUGCUGGUUACAUCCCCUUAUUUCUCUCCGUAAGUCCUGGGGAGGUGGCUUAAGGCAAUGACCAGUGUGGGCCACUUGAGCAGACCAUCCCGGAACCUCUCUGCCUGUUAACAGAGCCCAGGGAACAGCUCGGAAUUCUCACAGCAUUGGAAGCCCCCUUCUUGAGCUCUGCAAGGCCAGUCAAUUUAGCAGCUCACAUCUGGUUUCCUUUGGUGUGGGGUGUAAAGUAGAUCGCUCUUCCUGCUCUCAGCUGAUGCUGCCUCAUUGUAGCAUGUGUUUUCACUCUAGUGUUUUCACUCUACACUCUGUGUUUAUGAAUGAAUAGCCUGAGCUAUGUCACUAUAUCUGUUGAGAUGGAAAUGAGAAUUUGUAAAUGGGCCUCUGGCACUGCAAGAAUUGUUGUCAUAAGUGUUACAGCUUUCUGUUCAUUGCUGCUUCUCAGCUAGCACUGGCUUCAUCUUGGAAAAUCUUGGAAAUAUGGAAGAUGGUUCUAGCCCCCAAAUACAGAAUAAGUCUCUUGGUAGAUUGCCCUUAAGUCAUCAGCUCAAUCCUUCCUCAACAGGCUCCAUGAGGUAAGAAGUGGGAAUCCAGCUUGUGUGGGGGGGCUUUGAGGAGUGAAAUGAUUUGCCCAAAGUCACAGUGGGAAGCAGCAGAGCCAGGACUGGAACCCAGGCCAGACUCCAAACCGCAGGCUCCUUCCAUGCUUGAAAGGGCCGGACUCACGGUAGUUAAUAAAAUCAAUACAAAUCUUUUAUUAAAGAUCUACUCAUACCA